GGCAGAGUCGGUCCAGAACUGCCCGGACAGCGACGCACAGCGAGGAGCCAAAAUGGAAGAGGGUGCAAGUCCCCUCCUGGGGCCCCAGACGCCCCCUCCUUUCUUGCUGCCUGGAGCAGGGGCAGUGCUGUUAGUGGCUACUCCUGGUGUGAACAGCCCAUCCUGGCCACCUUCCACAGGAAACCUGACCUGAAGGACAGAAGAGGAAGGAAGCAGGCUUUGCCACAAAUGUCAGUGCAGAACUCUGGCUGGCCCCACCAAGAAGACAGCCCCAAGCCCCAGGAUCCAGGUCCACCAGCCAACUCAGACAGUGACUCAGGCCACCUGCCGGGGGAGGACCCUGAGGAUACCCAUGCUCAGGGUCCUGCAGUUCUGAGCUUGGGUUCCCUUUGCCUGGACACCAACCAAGCCCCCAACUGGACUGGACUUCAGACCCUCCUGCAGCAACUCCCUCCGCAGGACAUUGAUGAGCGCUACUGCCUGGCCCUUGGGGAGGAGGAGCGGGCCGAGCUGCAGCUCUUCUGUGCCAGGCGGAAGCAGGAAGCCCUGGGACAGGGGGUAGCCCGCCUGGUACUUCCCAAGCUUGAAGGACACACCUGUGAGAAGUGUAGGGAGCUGCUGAAGCCAGGGGAGUACGGAGUGUUUGCAGCCCGGGCAGGGGAACAGCGCUGCUGGCACCAGCCUUGCUUUGCCUGCCAGGCCUGUGGCCAGGCCCUGAUAAACCUCAUCUACUUCUACCAUGAUGGACAACUCUACUGCGGCCGUCAUCAUGCAGAGUUGCUGCGCCCGCGCUGCCCGGCUUGUGACCAGCUGAUCUUCUCCUGGCGCUGCACCGAGGCGGAGGGACAGCGCUGGCAUGAGAACCACUUCUGUUGCCAGGACUGCGCCGGGCCUCUGGGCGGGGGACGUUAUGCCCUGCCUGGGGGAAGCCCCUGCUGCCCCAGCUGCUUCGAGAACCGCUACUCGGAUGCAGGCUCGAGCUGGGCCGGGGCACUGGAAGGGCAGGCAUUCCUUGGGGAGACUGGACUCGACCGAACUGAAGGAAGGGACCAAACCUCGGUGAACUCUGCAACCCUCUCCCGAACACUCCUCGCUGCUGCCGGCGGUUCCAGCCUGCAAACUCAGAGGGGGCUGCCUGGAUCCAGUCCCCAGCAGGAGAACCGACCUGGGGACAAAGCGGAGGCACCCAAAGGGCAGGAGCAAUGCCGCCUGGAGACUAUUCGUGAUCCCAAGGACACCCCUUUCUCCACCUGCUCCUCCUCCUCUGACUCGGAACCUGAAGGAUUUUUCUUAGGCGAGCGCCUUCCCCAGUCCUGGAAGACCCCCGGAAGCCUCCAAGCAGAGGACAGCAACGCCUCUAAGACGCACUGCACCAUGUGCUAGUGGCGCAGCUCAGAGAGGGGAUGUGAGUGGGAGGAAAGGGGUCUGUAAAGCGGGAGAACAAGGCUAGCCUCCCCCUAACAAUCCUAGACUGAGACGCAGUCAGGCGCACGCCCGCAAGAGGCGGCGAGGUGACAAGUUUGGAGUGCGCCCCCUUCAGUACUGCGCGUUCUAAGACUUUUGGCGGAGACUUUCUUGGCAAAACCCAUUCCCCAAAGCUACGCUUCCCCUGCUGAGAUAGCCCCUACCCCCACCUCCACAGGCUGGGACAGCCCCGUCCCCACCAUCCUCCUCCCAAGCCAAUUAAAUGAUCACAGCACGCGUGA